CCAAGCCCCUUCUUUAUUUUGGAAUGGCCACCUGGCCAACUGGCACACAGGGAGAACUCAUGAAAGGAGGCGUGGCUCACUCCUGAAGGGAGAGGGACACAGGAGCAGCCUUGAUGCGCAACGCCCCCUCCAGGCCCCGAGUCCCUGUCCUUGGAGGAAGCAGGACUCCCAGGUGGGAGAGGUGAAGCAGAUGGCUUCCCCCACUGCAAGGAGGAAUCCCGGUGCUCUUCUCCACCAGCCUUCCCUUUGGUCGCCCCCUGGCGUCCGCGUCAUUGUGGGAACACUCGGGCGGGAUGUAUUUUAAAGGAGUGCCUGAUGCGUGUGGGUGUGGUGGGGUUGGGGGUGGGGGUGGGGCUGGGGGUGGUUGCAGCGGGGCCUAUGCAGGAUCCCGGUUGGAGGGGGCUGCAGAGGCUACUGCUGGGCCUGGUGUCGCCAUGGCAGCUGGAGAGCGGGCGACCGGUCGCUUGGCGUCCUGCUUGGGGUUGUUGCCCACAUCACCGAGCGAACGUUCCUGUCCCGCCCACUCACUGCGAGGCUGGGCAGGGCCGCUUGCCAGUUAAUUGUGGGGAUUAUUAUUUUUUUUUUUUUGUAGACGGAGUCGCGCUCUGUCUCCCAGGCUGGAGUGCAGUGGCGCUAUCUUGGCUCACUGCAAGCUCCGCCUCCAGGGUUCACGCCAUUCUCCUGCCUCAGCCUCCGGAGUAGCUGGGACUACAGGCGCCCGCCACCACGCCCGGCUAAUUUUUUGCGUUUUUUAGUAGAAACGAGGUUUCACCAUGUUAGCAAAGAUGGUCUCAAUCUCCUGACCUCGUGAUCCGCCCACCUAGGCCUCCCAAAAUGUUGGGAUUACAGGCGUGAGCCACUGCGCCCGGCCGGUUGUGGGGAUUAUCUGAGAGUUGCUGGAGUGUUCUGCACUUCCUUGCGAACCUUUUACCUGGGUGGGCAGGGGGAGAGGCCGAGUCAAGGGAAGGAGGCAGGAUGCCACACACGCCCUGCAGGGAGAGUCAUCUGCUGGGCACUGCGACACACAGAAAGCCAGGAGCCUGAGCCCCGCCCGCGGUUGUUGAACGGAGGGAGAAUGAACAACCGCUGACUUCCUGGUUCCUGGGUGCCGCAUCACUGCCCCUCUGCUCCGGGUCAAACCGGCUGUAUGCUUAGCUUCAGGAACAUGUGGCAGGUGGCAGCCCCCGGCCCCGUGGCAGUCUCCUGAAUAUUUACGCGUUGCUGAAUCUCCUGUGGACAAACCACCAAUAGGCCAGGACUGUCCUGUGGACAGACGGGAAAGAUUUGAUCACCAGGAGAUUUUUCGGGACAUUACCAAACCACUCAUUUUAGUGGCUGCCUCCGGGUGAUGAUGGCUGUGUGAACGACUGCCAUGGCCCACCGGAAGCUUGAGAGCGUGGGGAGCGGCAUGUUGGACCAUAGGGUGAGACCAGGUCCUGUCCCUCACAGCCAGGAGCCCGAGAGCGAGGACAUGGAGCUGCCCUUGGAGGGCUAUGUGCCCGAGGGCCUGGAGCUGGCUGCCCUGCGGCCAGAGAGCCCCGCGCCAGAGGAACAGGAGUGCCACAACCACAGCCCCGAUGGGGACUCCAGCUCUGACUACGUGAACAACACCUCUGAGGAGGAGGACUAUGACGAGGGCCUCCCUGAGGAGGAGGAGGGCAUCACCUACUACAUCCGCUACUGCCCUGAGGACGACAGCUACCUAGAGGGCAUGGACUGCAACGGGGAGGAGUACCUGGCCCACAGUGCACACCCUGUGGACACUGAUGAGUGCCAGGAGGCGGUGGAGGAGUGGACGGACUCGGCGGGCCCGCACCCCCACGGCCACGAGGCUGAAGGCAGCCAGGACUACCCAGACGGCCAACUGCCCAUUCCGGAGGAUGAGCCCUCCGUCCUUGAGGCCCAUGACCAGGAAGAAGAUGGUCACUACUGUGCCAGCAAAGAGGGCUACCAGGACUACUACCCCGAGGAGGCCAACGGGAACACCGGCGCCUCCCCCUACCGCCUGAGGCGUGGGGAUGGGGACCUGGAGGACCAGGAGGAGGACAUUGACCAGAUCGUGGCAGAGAUCAAGAUGAGUCUGAGCAUGACCAGCAUCACCAGCGCCAGUGAGGCCAGCCCCGAGCAUGGGCCUGAGCCAGGGCCUGAGGACUCUGUAGAGGCCUGCCCACCCAUCAAGGCCAGCUGCAGCCCCAGCAGGCACGAGGCGAGGCCCAAGUCGCUGAACCUCCUUCCCGAGGCCAAGCACCCCGGAGACCCCCAGAGAGGCUUCAAGCCCAAGACCAGGACCCCAGAAGAGAGGCUGAAGUGGCCCCACGAGCAGGUUUGCAAUGGUCUGGAGCAGCCAAGGAAGCAGCAGCGCUCUGAUCUCAAUGGACCUGUUGACAAUAACAACAUUCCAGAGACAAAGAAGGUGGCAUCAUUUCCAAGUUUUGUGGCUGUUCCAGGGCCCUGCGAACCAGAAGACCUCAUCGACGGGAUCAUCUUUGCUGCCAAUUACCUGGGGUCCACCCAGCUGCUAUCAGAACGGAACCCUUCCAAAAACAUCAGAAUGAUGCAAGCGCAGGAGGCCGUCAGCCGGGUCAAGGUAGAGAAUUCUGAGGGGGAUGCCCAGACGCUGACGGAAGUGGACCUCUUCAUUUCCACCCAGAGGAUCAAGGUUUUAAAUGCAGACACGCAGGAAACCAUGAUGGACCACGCCUUGCGUACCAUCUCCUACAUCGCCGACAUUGGGAACAUUGUAGUGCUGAUGGCCAGACGCCGCAUGCCCCGGUCAGCCUCUCAGGACUGCAUCGAGACCACGCCCGGGGCCCAGGAAGGCAAGAAGCAGUAUAAGAUGAUCUGCCAUGUGUUCGAGUCGGAGGAUGCCCAGCUCAUCGCCCAGUCUAUCGGCCAGGCCUUCAGCGUGGCCUACCAGGAGUUCCUGCGAGCCAAUGGCAUCAACCCCGAAGACUUGAGCCAGAAGGAAUACAGCGACAUCAUCAACACCCAGGAGAUGUACAACGACGACCUCAUCCACUUCUCAAACUCGGAGAACUGCAAGGAGCUGCAGCUGGAGAAGCACAAGGGCGAGAUCCUGGGCGUGGUGGUGGUGGAGUCGGGCUGGGGCUCCAUCCUGCCCACGGUGAUCCUGGCCAACAUGAUGAAUGGCGGCCCGGCUGCCCGCUCGGGGAAGCUGAGCAUCGGGGACCAGAUCAUGUCCAUCAAUGGCACCAGCCUGGUGGGGCUGCCCCUCGCCACCUGCCAAGGCAUCAUCAAGGGCCUGAAGAACCAGACACAGGUGAAGCUCAACAUUGUCAGCUGUCCCCCGGUCACCACGGUCCUUAUCAAGCGGCCAGACCUCAAGUACCAGCUGGGCUUCAGCGUGCAGAAUGGAAUUAUCUGCAGCCUCAUGAGAGGGGGCAUUGCUGAGCGAGGGGGCGUCCGUGUGGGCCACCGCAUCAUCGAGAUCAACGGGCAGAGCGUGGUGGCCACAGCCCACGAGAAGAUAGUCCAAGCUCUGUCCAACUCGGUCGGAGAGAUCCACAUGAAGACCAUGCCCGCCGCCAUGUUCAGGCUCCUCACGGGUCAGGAGACCCCGCUGUACAUCUAGGCCACCCCAGCCUGGCCACGCAGCCAGGACACCGGGCAGGGCCGCCCGGGCCCAGAGGAGCUGGGAGCCGGGCCGCAGACUUGACCCCGACGCCACAGCCCAGCCACGGACGCUGGCUCCCCAAAGGGUGUGCCCUCACCACCCACUUGAUUUUUUUCAUUUUGCCAAAAAGGGGUAUGUCUUUAUCAAAGGAGAGUCACAGAACAAAUGUUUGUUUGUAAAGCGUUCCAAGUAUUUUGCCACGUUCUGGACUGUCUUCUCCCUGCACAAGCCAGGGUGUGUCUCGGUAGCUGUGCGUGGUGUGGAGUGUGUGUCUUUCCUCCCUGAAGCUGUGCGGAGCGAACUGGCGCCUCCGAGGGACGCGGCUCCCGGGGCAGGGCAGCCGUCACCCCUGCCUCCCGCCCCCUUGGCUGGGACGUCUGGGGUCCUGUGGGGCCCCCACAAUGGUCCCAAACAGCUGCCUCUGCCACUGACUGCAGGGACACGGGCAGCCUGGCUCCCAGGACACGACUUGUAAUGAAAGUUUGGGGACAUGUGAUUGAUUGAUUGAUUGAUUGUAAAUAAAGGAUGAUGGCCACAACAUGAAAACUCCAUAUUUAUUUAGAUGCUAUUAUUACUGUUUGGACUUUUAUUUUGGCAGGCUUUUUUCCAGACUCUAGGGUUUUCCAAUGUGACUAAUGACCACACCUGCCUCUCCCGUCGUCUCUUCUGGGCACCCUCCCACCCGGCUGCAUACCCGGCCAGGGCUCCCACAGAGACAAGGAGGGCACAGGUGUCUGCCCCCUCUUUAAAAUCGAUCUACACACAUCCACGCACAUGCGACCCCGAGGAAACGAAACCCACUCUAGAAAACGCGACCUUGGCCGCACCUAAAGCAGCCAGCCGUGAGUGCAGACCCCUUGGCCAGCGUGGCGCAGUGGCCCUGAGCAGUAGUGGCAUGUGUGUAGAUCAAGUCGGAUCUAGUCCAGCUCGGUUCAUUAGCGAUCCAUGUAAUCUGACGUCAUCUUGUCUCGAAGUCUCUUUUUUUGGCCCAGGCCUUGAAGAAUACACUGUGACUUAAGAAGCCUUACCACGCAGUAACUAAAGCUUUAGGAUGACUGUAUUCGAGGAGUGCCGUGUGUUGCAUGCAGCUACCCGUAGGAAGACUUCGCGCAUAUCACUAAUAAACCUGAAGUCGUGAUGAAAA